GCGCGUACACUGUCUGGGGAGGUGCGGUGGGAUUGCUGGGCAGUACUGGGGCCCACCUGGGGUUCCUAAUAUGAUGUCAUCUGCAGGCAUAGGCAGCAAGGAAGGUUUUCUACAGCCAUGUUCAGCUGCUGAGCAGGGUUGGGAUUUGGCCACAGGUGGCAGACUCUAGGGGCCCAUGGUCCCCACCUCCUGGUGUUCACACCCUGGUUUAGUCCCCUCCCUUUGAGUGUAGGCAGGCAGGACCCAGGACUGACCUCCAGCUGACAGAAUACAGCAAAGUGGUGGAUGUCCCCCUGACACGUAAUAGCCUAUAAAACUCUGCCUCACUGCUGCUCGCUCUCCAGAUGCUCCUUGUUGCCUGAAAAGGCAAGCCAACAUACUGGAGGAGCCCACAUGGUGAGGAUGCAGGAGCCUGUUGGGGUGAAGGGGGCCUCUGAGGGGGCCUCCUGUAACAAAACACCAUAAACUUCUUGCUGGCCCACAGCCAGCAAGAAGCUGCAGCCCUGAGUCAUGCAGCCACGAGGACAUGGAUCCUGUCUGCACUGAGUGACCUUGGCAGCAGAUUUUUCCCCAGUUGAGCUUCCAGAUGAGAUCACAGCCCAGUGGCCCCUUGAGAUCCCAAGCAGACAACCCAGUUGAGCCACCCUGGCCUUGACCCACAGAAACUCUGAGAUUAUACACGUGUGUGCUUUUUAACAGGUACACUUUGUGGUGAUUUGUUUUGCAGCAAUAAAAAACUCGUUUAUCAGGUAAGUUUGAGAGAAUGAGUUGGGGCAAGUAAGAGGAGGGUGUUUGCUGGACCAGAGAGGCUCCACUGGGAAAGAGGGGAGUGAGGUCUUGGAGAAGGGACAUGGCCUGAAAGAGAAUGGACAUUUGUUGCACUAAGGGUGGGUGGUAUGUUCCUGUGUGAGUCCAUUCAUGCUGCUGUAACAAAACAUCAUAAACUGAUGACUUAUGCCACAAACAUAAUUUCUCACAGUUUGGGAGGCUGUGAAGUCUCAGAUCACAGCACCAACAGAUUCCGUGUCUGGGGAGGCCCACCUCCUGGUUCACAGACAGCAUCUUCUCGCCGUGUCCACACAUGGUGGAGAGAGGAGCUGAGCUCUCCCACGACUCUCAGAAGGGUCUGGAGCUGAUUCAUGAGAGCUCUACCCUCAGGGCCUCUCCAAAUCCCAGUCACCUCCCUGAGACCCCACCUCUGAAUACCAUCCCAUUACAGGGCAGGGUUUCAGCCUCUGAGUUUGUUGGAGGGCACAUACACAUUCAGUCUGUGGCAAUUCCAAUGGCAUGUUCUUCUAAAGAAGCUGGGUGUUUUAGGAGGGGCAAUGGCGCCCUGGAAUUGUCAAUGGAGAGCAGGAGGACCCCCUCUAAAGUCUCAGCAGGACCAGUUACAUAAUUUGUGAGGCCCUUUGUUCAAAAACCAGGGAAAAUGCCAUUAAUGGUAAGGAUAAAGUUUUCUCCUUUCUUCCAUAGUCUCUCUCUCUUGGCUUGUCAUGGUGCUUUUAAAUUGGUAUUUAAUGUCAUUAUUCUAAAUAAAAAAAUUUAAAUUUUAAAUUGUUAGCAUUACUUUUACUAGUCAUCUUUAUAUCAUGCCACAUCAGUUUCAAAUGCAAAUAUUGAAACAUUUAGCUCAUGCGUGGAAUUUGUGAAAUCAGACAACUUUUUUAUAGCUGGUAUGUACAUUUGUACUUUGUUCUUACCAGGUAGUGGAGCCACUGUCUAAAACCAAUGCAACUGUUUUAUCUCACUUUUAUGAUACAAGAACAUUCUGCCGACAUGGCCUGCCUUCGGCUCACUGGUUUGUGAGUGAUCACUCUCAGCAUAAGUGGUUGGUUAAAGCAGGGAAAUAACAAUGGUGAGAAGGAUAUAUGGACUUCCUUGGUCGUUCAGGUUUCUUCGAAUGUCAUGUUUUUCUAUAUUUGAAGUAAGUUCUGGCUCCACCAGGAAGUGUGCGUCUGGGGCUGUCAGUGCUUGGCUUACUCAGCUGUAGCCAUCACACGUCUUGUACUUGCUUUGAGUCACAGCAAACUCCUUUCAUCCUGGGUCCACUGGAAUUCUGUGCUCAUGGGGCAUUGUGAAGACUGUAUGUGAAACAGGCGAUUAGGAGUGGUGAUACACUACUGUGCUAACUCCAGCCCCAGCACGUGCCUCUGCAUCUCAGCGCCAGACAUCCUGCAUGGCCAAAGUGCACAGUCAGUCCUGGCUUCCCAGCAACCCUGGACAGCAAACCAAGUGGCUGCAAGGCCAAAGGUCAUUUCUGGUGCUGUCGGCUGCUUGAAAAUGCAAAAAAUAAAAUGAGAGAAGACUGGCAGUGGAGCAUGCAUCUGGAGGGCAGAGACGGCAGGCGGUACCCCGGCGCGCCGGCGGUGGAGCUCCUGCAGACGUCCGUGCCCAGCGGACUCGCUGAACUUGUGGCCGGCAAGCGCAGGCUUCCUCGGGGAGCCGGUGGAGCUGACCCCUCGCACUCCUGCCCCAGGGGGGCUGCCGGGCAGAGCUCUUGGGCUCCUGCAGGCCAGGAGUUUGCUUCAUUCCUCACAAAAGGGAGGUCUCACUCUUCUUUGCCCCAGAUGUCCAGCUCCAGGUCUAAAGAUUCCUGCUUUACAGAAAACACUCCUUUGCUGAGGAAUUCCUUACAGGAGAAAGGGUCACGGUGCAUACCUGUUUACCAUCCAGAGUUCAUCACUGCUGAAGAGUCUUGGGAAGACAGCUCUGCUGACUGGGAGCGAAGAUACCUGCUAAGCAGGGAGGUGUCUGGUCUGUCUGCAUCUGCCUCCUCCGAGAAGGGAGACCUUCUGGACAGCCCGCACAUCCGACUCCGUCUUUCCAAGCUGAGGCGCUGUGUGCAGUGGCUGAAAGUCAUGGGCCUGUUUGCCUUUGUGGUGCUGUGUUCUAUUUUGUUCAGCCUAUAUCCGGAUCAAGGAAAGCUCUGGCAGCUGUUGGCCUUAUCACCGCUGGAGAACUACUCCGUGAACCUUAGCAGCCACGUGGACUCCACGCUGCUGCAGGUGGACCUGGCAGGGGCCCUAGUGGCCAGUGGGCCGAGUCGUCCUGGGAGGGAAGAGCACAUCGUGGUGGAGCUGACCCAGGCUGACGCUUUGGGCUCCAGGUGGCGGCGGCCACAGCAGGUCACUCACAACUGGACGGUGUAUUUAAAUCCGAGGAGAAGCGAGCACUCAGUGAUGAGCAGGACCUUUGAGGUACUGACCAGAGAGACGGUGUCCAUCAGCAUCCGGGCCUCCCUGCAGCAGACCCAGGCUGUCCCUCUUUUGAUGGCUCAUCAGUACCUCCGCGGAAGUGUAGAAACCCAGGUGACCAUCGCGACGGCCAUCCUCGCGGGCGUCUACGCGCUGAUCAUAUUUGAGAUCGUGCACAGAACUCUGGCGGCCAUGCUGGGUUCCCUUGCAGCACUGGCAGCACUGGCUGUGAUUGGCGAUAGACCCAGCCUGACCCAUGUGGUGGAGUGGAUUGAUUUUGAGACGCUGGCCCUGCUGUUUGGCAUGAUGAUCUUAGUAGCCAUAUUUUCAGAAACGGGAUUUUUCGAUUAUUGUGCUGUAAAGGCAUACCGGCUCUCCCGGGGACGGGUGUGGGCCAUGAUCAUCAUGCUCUGUCUCAUCGCGGCCGUCCUCUCUGCCUUCUUGGACAACGUCACCACCAUGCUCCUCUUCACGCCUGUGACCAUAAGGUUGUGUGAGGUGCUCAACCUUGAUCCAAGACAAGUCCUGAUUGCAGAAGUGAUCUUCACAAACAUUGGAGGAGCUGCCACUGCCAUCGGGGACCCUCCAAAUGUCAUUAUUGUUUCCAACCAAGAGCUGAGGAAGAUGGGCCUGGACUUUGCCGGAUUCACUGCACACAUGUUCAUUGGGAUUUGCCUUGUUCUCCUGGUCUGCUUUCCGCUCCUCAGACUCCUUUACUGGAACAGAAAGCUUUAUAACAAGGAACCCAGUGAGAUUGUUGAACUGAAGCACGAGAUUCACGUCUGGCGCCUGACUGCUCAGCGCAUCAGCCCGGCCAGCCGCGAGGAGACAGCUGUGCGCCGCCUGCUGCUGGGGAAGGUGCUGGCACUGGAGCACCUGCUCGCCCGGAGGCUGCACACCUUCCACAGACAGAUCUCACAGGAGGACAAAAAUUGGGAGACCAAUAUCCAAGAACUCCAAAAAAAGCAUAGGAUAUCUGACGGGAUUCUGCUCGCCAAAUGCCUGACAGUGUUGGGAUUUGUUAUCUUCAUGUUUUUCCUCAAUUCGUUUGUCCCUGGCAUUCAUCUUGAUCUUGGAUGGAUUGCUAUUCUGGGUGCCAUCUGGUUGCUAAUUUUAGCUGAUAUUCAUGAUUUUGAGAUAAUUCUACACAGAGUGGAAUGGGCAACCCUUCUGUUUUUUGCAGCGCUCUUUGUUCUGAUGGAGGCAUUGGCACAUCUCCACUUAAUAGAAUAUGUUGGAGAACAAACUGCUUUGCUAAUAAAGAUGGUCCCAGAGGAGCAGCGCCUCAUAGCCGCCAUUGUCCUGGUGGUGUGGGUCUCAGCCCUGGCGUCGUCCCUGAUUGACAACAUCCCGUUCACUGCUACCAUGAUUCCCGUGCUCCUGAACCUGAGCCACGACCCUGAGGUUGGCCUGCCCGCACCGCCGCUCAUGUAUGCCCUGGCCUUCGGUGCUUGCCUGGGAGGUAACGGGACACUGAUUGGCGCGUCGGCAAACGUCGUGUGUGCAGGGAUUGCAGAACAGCAUGGAUAUGGGUUCUCCUUCAUGGAAUUUUUCAGGCUGGGCUUCCCAAUGAUGGUUGUGUCCUGCACUGUUGGGAUGUGUUAUCUCCUUGUGGCUCAUGUGGUGGUGGGAUGGAAUUAAUAGACAUCCAUCUAUUGCUCGAAGACUAAAGGAAACUUCAUCCAUCACAACCCAUUAGUCAUAAAACUACCCUGACCCCACUGUUUGAAGAAGAAAAGGUGCUUACCCUGGAGAUGCUACAGAGACACAGUGGAAUAGACCUUGACACUAACACUCUAAUUCAAGCGAAUGUUGGAACACCAUGACCUCCUCUGUGUGUCCUUUCUCCCCAAGGACAAAAUGUAGAAAGAUGUGAGAUAACUUACUCAAGAUUCCCCUCCAGAAAAAUACGUAUGUUUAAAAACCCUUCCUGCUAUACAUAGGAAAAGACACACAUCCACCUAAAAUUGACUGUACUGUUUAACUGUCAAUUCUCCUGAGGCUAAACACAGUUUGUUUUUCUUGUAAUCACUUUUCAUGUUAAAAUAAUCAGCAUUCAAAUUGUAUGCUUUCUGAAUAUAGACUUUCUGGGAAAAGGUUUACUGCUCGUAAGGAAACAUUUUAUGUAUUAAAAUAAACUGUUCCUUGAUAAAA